GCGGCGCGGCCGUAAAGCGCCAUUACGCAGAGAGAAAGUUACGAGGUUCGUGGCCGCGGUUUCCCCAGGCAGCUGGCGCUGGAGGCUUCGGCGUCACGUGCUGGUCUGGAUUUUUCUCGAUGCACUGGGGAAAGCGGUGGACUCUUAUCGUGGGAGGGCUCUUGAUCUGUGAUUUAUAGAUAGGCACAGCUACUCCCGUUCGGGAACCCAACGGCAGACAGGUCCUAGUGCCCAUCAGAUACCCGCGGCCGGGACUCGGAGCUGUGGGGUGUGGGGAGGCGGAGGCACCAACUAAGAGCGACCUAGCAUCGCAAAGCCGCCCUCGGGGCGCUCAUGGCGGGACGCCUCCUGGGAAAGGCUUUAGCCGCGGUGUCUCUCUCUCUGGCCUUGGCCUCUGUGACUAUCAGGUCCUCGCGCUGCCGCGGCAUCCAGGCGUUCAGAAACUCGUUUUCAUCUUCUUGGUUUCAUCUUAAUACCAACGUCAUGUCUGGUUCUAAUGGUUCCAAAGAAAAUUCUCACAAUAAGGCUCGGACGUCUCCUUACCCAGGUUCAAAAGUUGAACGAAGCCAGGUUCCUAAUGAGAAAGUGGGCUGGCUUGUUGAGUGGCAAGACUAUAAGCCUGUGGAAUACACUGCAGUCUCUGUCUUGGCUGGACCCAGGUGGGCAGAUCCUCAGAUCAGUGAAAGUAAUUUUUCUCCCAAGUUUAACGAAAAGGAUGGGCAUGUUGAGAGAAAGAGCAAGAAUGGCCUGUAUGAGAUUGAAAAUGGAAGACCGAGAAAUCCUGCAGGACGGACUGGACUGGUGGGCCGGGGGCUUUUGGGGCGAUGGGGCCCAAAUCACGCUGCAGAUCCCAUUAUAACCAGAUGGAAAAGGGAUAGCAGUGGAAAUAAAAUCAUGCAUCCUGUUUCUGGGAAGCAUAUCUUACAAUUUGUUGCAAUAAAAAGGAAAGACUGUGGAGAAUGGGCAAUCCCAGGGGGGAUGGUGGAUCCAGGAGAGAAGAUUAGUGCCACACUGAAAAGAGAAUUUGGUGAGGAAGCUCUCAACUCCUUACAGAAAACCAGUGCUGAGAAGAGAGAAAUAGAGGAAAAGUUGCACAAACUCUUCAGCCAAGACCACCUAGUGAUAUAUAAGGGAUAUGUUGAUGAUCCUCGAAACACUGAUAAUGCAUGGAUGGAGACAGAAGCUGUGAACUACCAUGACGAAACAGGUGAGAUAAUGGAUAAUCUUAUGCUAGAAGCUGGAGAUGAUGCUGGAAAAGUGAAAUGGGUGGACAUCAAUGAUAAACUGAAGCUUUAUGCCAGUCACUCUCAAUUCAUCAAACUUGUGGCUGAGAAACGAGAUGCACACUGGAGCGAGGACUCUGAAGCUGACUGCCAUGCGUUGUAGCUGAUGGUCUCCGUGUAAGCCAAAGGCCCACAGAGGAGCAUAUACUGAAAAGAAGGCAGUAUCACAGAAUUUAUACUAUAAAAAGGGCAGGGUAGGCCACUUGGCCUAUUUACUUUCAAAACAAUUUGCAUUUAGAGUGUUUCGCAUCAGAAUAACAUGAGUAAGAUGAACUGGAACACAAAAUUUUCAGCUCUUUGGUCAAAAGGAAUAUAAGUAAUCAUAUUUUGUAUGUAUUCGAUUUAAGCAUGGCUUAAAUUAAAUUUAAACAACUAAUGCUCUUUGAAGAAUCAUAAUCAGAAUAAAGAUAAAUUCUUGAUCAGCUAUAACUUCUGUUUCAUCUAGUUCUUGUUUGUCAAUGCCUUCCCUCCCGCUCCCCAUCUUCUGAGGCCUGAAGGAUGUUCCUGCCACAUCAAACUCCUUUAGGCAGAGUACCGCCACUGGAUGUAUAGUUUAAUGUUUCAUCUGAUUUUUCUUUAAAUUAUUUCCUUCACAUUUUGCUUCACAUGAUCUUGUUGAAGCUAAUUUUGAAAAUGGAAACUAUGUUUUCUUGACUUUAGAAGCAUUAGUUUUAAGAGGAAAUUUCAGCCACUAGUCAAUAGAGAUCAAAAUCAGUGAACAAGAGCUGAUACUCUCAUUUUCAAAAAUUCUGAAUUAAAAAAAGUCCAGGAAGUUAGUAAUUUAAAUCAGUAUGUUCAUUUCACUCUAGUGAAACUACUAUAUGUUGUAAAUUAGUUAAAAAUGGAUGUUCAGAAAAGAAUUGAAAUCAGGACAAAAAAUUACAGAUGCUAGUGAGGUUGUAGAGAAAAAGGAAUGCUUAUACGCUGUUAGUGGGAGUGUAAAUUGGUCCAACCAUUGUGGAAGAGAGUGUAGAGAGUCCUCAAAUAUUUAAAGAUAUUUGACCCAGUAAUCCCAUUACUAGGUAUAUACCCGAAGGAAUAUAAAUUGUUCUAUUAUAAACACAUACUCACGUGUAUGUUCAUUGCUGCACUAUUCACAAUAGCGAAGACAUGAAAUCAACCUAAAUGUUCAUCAGUGAUAGACUGGAUAAAGACAAUGUGGUAUAUGUACACCAUGGAAUACUAUGCAGCCGUAAAAAAGAAUAAGAUCAUGUCCUCUGAAAAGACAUGGGUGGAGCUGGAGGCCAUUAUCCUUAGCAAACUAAUGCAAGAACAGAAAACCAAACACUGCAUGUUCUCUUAUAAGUGAGAGCUAAAUGGUGAGAACACAUGGACAUGGGAACAACACAUUCUGGGGUCUAUUGGAGGGUGGGAGGAGGGAGAGGAUCAGGAAAAAUAACUAAUGAGUACUAGGCUUAAUACCUUGGUGAUGAAAUUAUCUGUACAACAAACCCUCAUGACACAAGUUUACCUAUGUAACAAACCUGCACAUGUACCCCUGUACUUAACAACAAAAUAAACACAAAGGAAAAUGUUA